AUCCAUUUGUUCUCAAGAGGUAGCAAGAAACAGUAUCCACAGUGGACUCCGGGGCUCCUACAGACUUGGCACAGCUUCCUACAGUCUUGAAACAGCCCUGUUGUUCUGUCAUGGCCAGUGGGCAGUUUGUGAACAAACUGCAAGAGGAAGUGAUCUGCCCCAUCUGCCUGGACAUUCUGCAGAAACCUGUCACCAUCGACUGUGGGCACAAUUUCUGCCUCAAAUGCAUCACUCAGAUUGGGGAAACAUCAUGUGGAUUUUUCAAAUGUCCCCUCUGCAAAACUUCCGUAAGGAAGAACGCAAUCAGGUUCAACUCGCUGUUGCGGAAUCUGGUGGAGAAAAUCCAAGCUCUACAAGCCUCUGAGGUGCAGUCCAAAAGGAAAGAGGCUACAUGCCCGAGGCACCAGGAGAUGUUCCACUAUUUCUGCGAGGAUGAUGGGAAGUUCCUCUGUUUUGUGUGUCGUGAAUCCAAGGACCACAAAUCCCAUAAUGUCAGCUUGAUCGAAGAAGCUGCCCAGAAUUAUCAGGGGCAGAUUCAAGAGCAGAUCCAAGUCUUGCAGCAAAAGGAGAAGGAGACAGUACAAGUGAAGGCACAAGGUGUACACAGGGUCGAUGUCUUCACGGACCAGGUAGAACAUGAGAAGCAAAGGAUCCUCACAGAAUUUGAACUCCUGCAUCAAGUCCUAGAGGAGGAGAAGAAUUUCCUGCUAUCACGGAUUUACUGGCUGGGUCAUGAGGGAACGGAAGCGGGGAAACACUAUGUUGCCUCCACUGAGCCACAGUUGAACGAUCUCAAGAAGCUCGUUGAUUCCCUGAAGACCAAGCAGAACAUGCCACCCAGGCAGCUGCUGGAGGAUAUCAAAGUCGUCUUGUGCAGAAGUGAAGAGUUUCAGUUUCUCAACCCAACCCCUGUUCCUCUGGAACUGGAGAAAAAACUCAGUGAAGCAAAAUCAAGACAUGACUCCAUCACAGGGAGCCUAAAAAAAUUCAAAGACCAACUCCAGGCUGAUAGGAAAAAAGAUGAAAACAGAUUCUUCAAAAGCAUGAAUAAAAAUGACAUGAAGAGCUGGGGCUUGUUACAGAAAAAUAAUCAUAAAAUGAACAAAACCUCAGAGCCCGGGUCAUCUUCUGCAGGCGGCAGAACUACAUCGGGGCCACCAAAUCACCACUCUUCAGCCCCAUCCCACUCCCUGUUUCGGGCCUCGUCUGCUGGGAAAGUCACUUUUCCAGUAUGUCUCCUGGCCUCUUAUGAUGAGAUUUCUGGUCAAGGAGCGAGCUCUCAGGAUACGAAGACAUUUGACGUUGCGCUGUCCGAGGAGCUCCAUGCGGCACUGAGUGAGUGGCUGACAGCGAUCCGGGCUUGGUUUUGUGAGGUUCCUUCAAGCUAAGCCAGCUCAGAGAACACGGGGAGCGGUGGUGCUACACGGACUUCGGAGCAUAGAGUGGCGCUGAGUGAGUGGCUGAGACCGACCACGGUUCUUGACUUAGUGGAAUUGGGUCGAAGGAGUGGAGAAUGGGAGGGCUCGGGCUACUGAGAGUGGAGAUGGGGGCGGGGGUGGUGGUGAAGAGAGUUGGAGAAGGAAUGGACGAAUUCUUGAGCAAAAGGAGGGGAAGAGACAAUCUCCAGCCACCCGCCCCACGCUUGACUUCUUAUCACUUUGGCUGUGGUGCCGCCUAGUGGAAAAAGGAAGUCCCUGCAGCAGUCCCCGCACUCUUUAAGCAGCUGUUUACCGAAGGCACCAGUUCAGCCAGGAGUGAAAUCCGGAGAGGAGCAACGCCAGCCUGGGUCACAGUCCAUCAAACCCCAUGAGCCCGACCACUCUCGCUCUUCCUUACAUUCCCACGUCCCCCUUCUCUCCCAACCCCUCAUAUCAGCAAGGGAAAUUAAUUAAUGAGAUUUGAUAAAUCAGUAGAUAGAAUGAGGUCCCCAUUCUGAAAUAUUUAGCAGACUGGAACCACCACGCAAGCCUCUGUAGGGGGUGGAUGGAGACACUUCUAACUUUAAUAAACUGCGACUGAACGUGGAA